ACUCAGGGUUAGGAGGUCUGGGCGAGAAGCAACUAGGGCCCUCAUCACUUCGCCGCCGAAUCCCCGGCGCCGCCCAGCGGGGCAGAGCCAGGCCAGGGCCGCCCGCCCAACCUGGUCCGCUGCCUCUUCGGCCAUGGAAGCUGCCGGCAGCCCUGCGGCUACGGAGACAGGCAAGUAUAUCGCGUCAACACAGCGACCUGACGGGACCUGGCGCAAGCAGCGGAGGGUGAAAGAAGGAUAUGUGCCCCAGGAGGAGGUCCCAGUAUAUGAAAACAAGUAUGUGAAGUUUUUCAAGAGUAAACCAGAGUUGCCCCCAGGGCUAAGCCCUGAGGCCACUGCUCCUGUCACCCCAUCCAGGCCUGAAGGUGGUGAACCAGGCCUCUCCAAGACAGCCAAACGUAACCUGAAGCGAAAGGAGAAGAGGCGGCAGCAGCAAGAGAAAGGAGAGGCAGAGGCCUUGAGCAGGACUCUUGAUAAGGUGUCCCUGGAAGAGACAGCCCAACUCCCCAGUGCUCCACAGGGCUCUCGGGCAGCCCCCACAGCUGCAUCUGACCAGCCUGACUCAGCUGCCACCACUGAGAAAGCCAAGAAGAUAAAGAACCUAAAGAAGAAACUCCGGCAGGUGGAAGAGCUGCAGCAGCGGAUCCAGGCUGGGGAAGUCAGCCAGCCUAGCAAAGAGCAGCUAGAAAAGCUAGCAAGGAGGAGGGCGCUAGAAGAGGAGUUAGAGGACUUGGAGUUAGGCCUCUGAGGCCUUUGGGGAAUAGGGAAUGGACUGCAGAACAAACCGUGGGGCUCUCUGGGGUCUGGGGGAAUACGGGCAACAGCAGUCAGGAGGGGUACCCCCCAUACUGGCUUACUUCCACCUCCUGCGGCCCAGCUCUGUCCUCCAGAGCCUAGCGUCUCCCUCAAUCCUUCCCUUUUCUUCCCAACUUCUACUUUUUGGACUUUCCCCCUCCCAUUCCCAGUGUUCAAAAUCUCAGUGACUACCCCAGGUACCUUUGCUGCUGAUUUGGGUGUCUUGUUUAAAAGAAAAUCAGGUGGGUGGGAAUCUCUUGGAGAACUGAGGCUGAGGGUAGAGGGAGUAUGCCCAAGUCUUGGAGUCUUGGUUCCUGUUCGCGGUGUUUAUGGGUUAUUUCCCUCUCCAUCCCUCAUUUUUUUUUUUUUUUUAAAAAAAGCAAAAAUGAGAAUAAACACAAGUAGACAUGUC